ACCACACAAAGCGGAAUGAGAUGGAUACUCACAGAUCCUGACACUGGAGACUUAGAAGUAUUUUCCUUCGCUUUCUGAUAUAUUUUGGAUGUAGUCGGCCUAGGACUUCAUAGAUACAUAAGCCGAUUCACAACCAACCAGCUCGAGAAACCGCGGAAUAUCGGCUUAGAGCCUGCCAUGGCGAAUCGGCUACAGCGCGGGGACCGCAGUCGGCUGCUGCUGCUGCUGUGCAUUUUCCUGGGGACGCUGCGGGGGUUCCGGGCCAGGCAGAUCCGAUAUUCGGUGCCAGAAGAGACCGAAAAGGGCUCCUUCGUGGGCAAUAUCUCCAAGGACCUGGGGCUGGAGCCCCGGGAGCUGGCGAAGCGCGGAGUCCGCAUCGUCUCCAGAGGGAAGACACAGCUUUUCGCUGUGAAUCCGCGAAGCGGCAGCUUGAUCACGGCAGGCAGGAUAGACCGGGAGGAGCUCUGUGAGACGGUGUCCUCCUGUUUUUUAAAUAUGGAACUUCUCGUGGAAGACACCUUGAAGAUUUACGGAGUGGAGGUGGAAAUAAUAGAUAUUAAUGAUAACGCCCCCAGCUUCCAGGAGGACGAAGUGGAGAUAAAAGUCAGUGAGCACGCAAUUCCUGGGGCGCGAUUUGCUCUUCCUAAUGCUAGGGAUCCAGAUGUGGGCGUGAACUCCCUCCAGAGCUACCAGCUCAGCCCUAAUAAUUACUUUUCCUUGCAACUGCGGGGCAGAACGGAUGGGGCCAAGAAUCCAGAGCUAGUACUGGAGGGAAGCCUGGACCGAGAGAAAGAGGCUGCUCACCUGCUCCUCCUCACAGCUUUAGAUGGAGGCGAUCCCAUCCGAAAGGGCGCAGUUCCCAUUCGUGUGGUGGUCCUCGAUGUAAAUGAUCACAUCCCAAUGUUUACACAGUCCGUAUAUCGCGUGAGUGUUCCAGAAAACAUCAGCUCCGGAACUCGGGUGCUGAUGGUUAAUGCAACGGAUCCAGACGAGGGAAUCAACGGGGAAGUAAUGUAUUCAUUUCGGAACAUGGAAAGCAAGGCUUCUGAAAUAUUCCAAUUGGAUUCACAAACUGGAGAAGUUCAAGUACGGGGGUCUCUGGAUUUUGAAAAAUAUAGAUUCUAUGAGAUGGAAAUUCAAGGCCAAGAUGGUGGAGGUCUCUUUACCACCACGACGAUGUUGAUCACUGUUGUGGAUGUGAAUGAUAACGCUCCAGAAAUAACUAUCACCUCUUCUAUUAAUUCAAUUCUGGAAAACUCUCCUCCAGGUACAGUGAUUGCUCUUCUAAAUGUGCAAGAUCAAGAUUCUGGAGAAAAUGGUCAAGUCUCCUGUUUUAUUCCUAACCACCUGCCUUUUAAAUUAGAAAAGACUUAUGGAAAUUAUUACAAAUUGAUAACAAGCAGAGUGCUGGACAGGGAGUUGGUCCAGAGCUACAAUAUAACGUUGACAGCCACAGACCAGGGAAGCCCGCCUUUGUCUGCAGAAACUCAUGUCUGGCUGAAUGUGGCAGAUGACAACGAUAACCCUCCCGUUUUUCCUCACUCCUCUUACUCUGCCUACAUUCCCGAAAACAACCCCAGGGGUGCCUCCAUCUUCUCAGUGACCGCCCUCGACCCGGACAGCAAACAGAAUGCCCUGGUCACUUACUCUCUGACGGAUGACACUGUCCAGGGGGUGCCUCUGUCCUCCUAUGUCUCUAUUAACUCCAACACUGGUGUUCUCUAUGCCCUACAAUCCUUCGACUAUGAGCAGUUUCGAGACUUAGAACUGAGAGUGAUAGCACGUGACAGCGGGGACCCGCCCCUCAGCAGCAACGUGUCGCUGAGCCUGUUCGUGCUGGACCAGAACGACAAUGCGCCCGAGAUCCUGUACCCUGCCCUCCCCACAGACGGCUCCACUGGCGUGGAGCUGGCGCCCCGCUCUGCGGAACCUGGCUACCUGGUGACCAAGGUGGUUGCGGUGGACAAAGAUUCAGGCCAGAACGCCUGGCUGUCCUAUCGCCUGCUUAAGGCCAGCGAGCCGGGACUCUUCGCGGUGGGGGAGCACACGGGCGAGGUGCGUACAGCGCGGGCACUGCUGGACAGAGACGCGCUCAAGCAGAGCCUCGUGGUGGCCGUCCAGGACCACGGCCAGCCCCCUCUCUCGGCCACCGUCACGCUCACCGUGGCUGUGGCCGACAGCAUCCCCGAAGUCCUGGCGGACCUCGGCAGCCUCGAGUCUCUGGCUAACUCUGAAACCUCAGACCUCUCGCUGUACUUGGUGGUGGCGGUGGCCGCAGUCUCCUGCAUCUUCCUGGUCUUUGUCAUCGUGCUGCUGGCACUCAGGCUGUGGCGCUGGCAUAAGUCACGCCUGCUGCAGGCUUCUGAAGGCGGGUUGGCAGGUAUGCCCACGUCACAUUUUGUAGGCGUGGACGGGGUACAGGCUUUCCUGCAAACCUAUUCCCACGAGGUCUCUCUCAUUGCGGACUCGCAGAAGAGUCACCUGAUUUUCCCCCAGCCCAACUAUGGGGACACGCUCAUCAGCCAGGAGAGCUGUGAGAAAAGCGAGCCACUCUUGAUAGCUGAAGACUCAGCUAUCAUUUUAGGCAAAUGUGACCCGACAAGUAAUCAGCAAGCCCCGCCCAACACGGACUGGCGUUUCUCUCAGGCCCAGAGACCCGGCACCAGCGGCUCCCAAAAUGGCGAUGACACCGGCACCUGGCCCAACAACCAGUUUGACACAGAGAUGCUGCAAGCCAUGAUCUUGGCGUCCGCCAGUGAAGCUGCUGAUGGGAGCUCCACCCUGGGAGGGGGUGCCGGCACCAUGGGAUUGAGCGCCCGCUACGGACCCCAGUUCACCCUGCAGCACGUGCCCGACUACCGCCAGAAUGUCUACAUCCCAGGCAGCAAUGCCACACUGACCAACGCAGCUGGCAAGCGGGAUGGCAAGGCCCCAGCAGGUGGCAAUGGCAACAAGAAGAAGUCGGGCAAGAAGGAGAAGAAGUAACAUGGAGGCCAGGCCAAGAGCCACAGGGCGGCCUCUCCCCAACCAGCCCAGCUUCUCCUUACCUGCACCCAGGCCUCAGAGUUUCAGGGCUAACCCCCAGAAUACUGGUAGGGGCCAAGGCCAUGCUCCCCUUGGGAAACAGAAACAAGUGCCCAGUCAGCACCUACCCCUUCCCCCCCAGGGGGUUGAAUAUGCAAAAGCAGUUCCGCUGGGAACCCCCAUCCAAUCAACUGCUGUACCCAUGGGGGUAGUGGGGUUACUGUAGACACCAAGAACCAUUUGCCACACCCCGUUUAGUUACAGCUGAACUCCUCCAUCUUCCAAAUCAAUCAGGCCCAUCCAUCCCAUGCCUCCCUCCUCCCCACCCCACUCCAACAGUUCCUCUUUCCCGAGUAAGGUGGUUGGGGUGUUGAAGUACCAAGUAACCUACAAGCCUCCUAGUUCUGAAAAGUUGGAAGGGCAUCAUGACCUCUUGGCCUCUCCUUUGAUUCUCAAUCUUCCCCCAAAGCAUGGUUUGGUGCCAGCCCCUUCACCUCCUUCCAGAGCCCAAGAUCAAUGCUCAAGUUUUGGAGGACAUGAUCACCAUCCCCAUGGUACUGAUGCUUGCUGGAUUUAGGGAGGGCAUUUUGCUACCAAGCCUCUUCCCAACGCCCUGGGGACCAGUCUUCUGUUUUGUUUUUCAUUGUUUGACGUUUCCACUGCAUGCCUUGACUUCCCCCACCUCCUCCUCAAACAAGAGACUCCACUGCAUGUUCCAAGACAGUAUGGGGUGGUAAGAUAAGGAAGGGAAGUGUGUGGAUGUGGAUGGUGGGGGCAUGGACAAAGCUUGACACAUCAAGUUAUCAAGGCCUUGGAGGAGGCUCUGUAUGUCCUCAGGGGACUGACAACAUCCUCCAGAUUCCAGCCAUAAACCAAUAACUAGGCUGGACCCUUCCCACUACAUAAUAGGGCUCAGCCCAGGCAGCCAGCUUUGGGCUGAGCUAACAGGACCAAUGGAUUAAACUGGCAUUUCAGUCCAAGGAAGCUCGAAGCAGGUUUAGGACCAGGUCCCCUUGAGAGGUCAGAGGGGCCUCUGUGGGUGCUGGGUACUCCAGAGGUGCCACUGGUGGAAGGGUCAGCGGAGCCCCAGCAGGAAGGGUGGGCCAGCCAGGCCAUUCUUAGUCCCUGGGUUGGGGAGGCAGGGAGCUAGGGCAGGGACCAAAUGAACAGAAAGUCUCAGCCCAGGAUGGGGCUUCUUCAACAGGGCCCCUGCCCUCCUGAAGCCUCAGUCCUUCACCUUGCCAGGUGCCGUUUCUCUUCCGUGAAGGCCACUGCCCAGGUCCCCAGUGCGCCCCCUAGUGGCCAUAGCCUGGUUAAAGUUCCCCAGUGCCUCCUUGUGCAUAGACCUUCUUCUCCCACCCCCUUCUGCCCCUGGGUCCCCGGCCAUCCAGCGGGGCUGCCAGAGAACCCCAGACCUGCCCUUACAGUAGUGUAGCGCCCCCUCCCUCUUUCGGCUGGUGUAGAAUAGCCAGUAGUGUAGUGCGGUGUGCUUUUACGUGAUGGCGGGUGGGCAGCGGGCGGCGGGCUCCGCGCAGCCGUCUGUCCUUGAUCUGCCCGCGGCGGCCCGUGUUGUGUUUUGUGCUGUGUCCACGCGCUAAGGCGACCCCCUCCCCCGUACUGACUUCUCCUAUAAGCGCUUCUCUUCGCAUAGUCACGUAGCUCCCACCCCACCCUCUUCCUGUGUCUCACGCAAGUUUUAUACUCUAAUAUUUAUAUGGCUUUUUUUCUUCGACAAAAAAAUAAUAAAACGUUUCUUCUGAAAA